GACAAGUGCCAAAAUGGCGAUGCCUACCACCUAGAACUGGAUUGUGCGCUGGCCGCCACCGCUGCCACCUGCUCAGAGUGAAAUAAUGAAGGUGGUCAACCUGAAGCAAGCCAUUUUGCAAGCCUGGAAGGAGCGCUGGAGUGACUACCAAUGGGCAAUCAACAUGAAGAAAUUCUUUCCUAAAGGAGCCACCUGGGAUAUUCUCAACCUGGCAGAUGCGUUACUAGAGCAGGCCAUGAUUGGACCAUCCCCCAAUCCUCUCAUCUUGUCCUACCUGAAGUAUGCCAUUAGUUCCCAGAUGGUGUCCUACUCUUCUGUCCUCACAGCCAUCAGUAAGUUUGAUGACUUUUCUCGGGACCUGUGUGUCCAGGCAUUGCUGGACAUCAUGGACAUGUUUUGUGACCGUCUGAGCUGUCACGGCAAAGCAGAGGAAUGCAUCGGACUGUGCCGAGCCCUUCUUAGCGCCCUCCACUGGCUGCUGCGCUGCACGGCAGCCUCUGCAGAGCGGCUGCGGGAGGGGCUGGAGGCCGGCACUCCAGCCGCUGGGGAGAAGCAGCUUGCCAUGUGCCUUCAGCGCCUGGAGAAAACCCUCAGCAGCACCAAGAACCGGGCCCUGCUGCACAUCGCCAAACUAGAGGAGGCCUCAUUGCACACAUCCCAGGGACUUGGGCAGGGUGGCACCCGAGCCAAUCAACCAACAGCUUCUUGGACUGCCAUCGAGCAUUCUCUCUUGAAACUUGGAGAGAUCCUGGCCAAUCUCAGCAACCCGCAGCUCCGGAGUCAGGCCGAGCAGUGUGGCACCCUCAUUAGGAGCAUCCCCACGAUGCUGUCUGUGCAUGCGGAGCAGAUGCACAAGACCGGCUUCCCCACUGUCCACGCCGUGAUCCUGCUCGAGGGCACCAUGAACCUGACAGGCGAGACGCAGUCCCUGGUGGAGCAGCUGACGAUGGUGAAGCGCAUGCAGCAUAUCCCCACCCCACUUUUUGUCCUGGAGAUCUGGAAAGCUUGCUUCGUGGGGCUCAUUGAGUCUCCCGAGGGUACGGAGGAGCUCAAGUGGACAGCUUUCACUUUCCUCAAGAUUCCACAGGUUUUGGUGAAGUUGAAGAAGUACUCUCAUGGAGACAAGGACUUCACUGAGGAUGUCAACUGUGCUUUUGAGUUCCUGCUGAAGCUCACCCCCUUGUUGGACAAAGCUGACCAGCGCUGCAACUGUGACUGUACAAACUUCCUGCUCCAAGAAUGUGGCAAGCAGGGGCUUCUGUCUGAGGCCAGCGUCAACAACCUUAUGGCUAAGCGCAAAGCGGACCGAGAGCACGCACCCCAGCAGAAAUCGGGAGAGAAUGCCAACAUCCAGCCCAACAUCCAGCUGAUCCUCCGGGCGGAGCCCACUGUCACAAACAUCCUCAAGACGAUGGAUGCAGACCACUCUAAGUCACCGGAGGGACUGCUGGGAGUCCUGGGCCACAUGCUGUCCGGGAAGAGUCUGGACUUGCUGCUGGCUGCCGCCGCCGCCACUGGAAAGCUGAAAUCCUUCGCCCGGAAAUUCAUCAAUUUGAAUGAAUUCACAACCUAUGGCAGCGAAGAAAGCACCAAACCGGCCUCCGUCCGGGCCCUGCUGUUUGACAUCUCCUUCCUCAUGCUGUGCCAUGUGGCCCAGACCUAUGGUUCAGAGGUGAUUCUGUCCGAGUCGCGCACAGGAGCUGAGGUGCCCUUCUUCGAGACCUGGAUGCAGACCUGCAUGCCUGAGGAGGGCAAGAUCCUGAACCCUGACCACCCCUGCUUCCGCCCCGACUCCACCAAAGUGGAGUCCCUGGUGGCCCUGCUCAACAACUCCUCGGAGAUGAAGCUAGUGCAGAUGAAGUGGCAUGAGGCCUGUCUCAGCAUCUCAGCCGCCAUCUUGGAAAUCCUCAAUGCCUGGGAGAAUGGGGUCCUGGCCUUCGAGUCCAUCCAGAAAAUCACUGAUAACAUCAAAGGGAAGGUAUGCAGUCUGGCGGUGUGUGCUGUGGCUUGGCUUGUGGCCCACGUCCGGAUGCUGGGGCUGGAUGAGCGUGAGAAGUCGCUGCAGAUGAUCCGCCAGCUGGCAGGGCCACUGUUUAGUGAGAACACCCUGCAGUUCUACAAUGAGAGGGUGGUGAUCAUGAACUCGAUCCUGGAGCGCAUGUGUGCCGACGUGCUGCAGCAGACAGCCACGCAGAUCAAGUUUCCCUCCACCGGGGUGGACACAAUGCCCUACUGGAACCUGCUGCCCCCCAAGCGGCCCAUCAAAGAGGUGCUGACGGACAUUUUUGCCAAGGUGCUGGAGAAGGGCUGGGUGGACAGCCGCUCCAUCCACAUCUUUGACACCCUGCUGCACAUGGGCGGCGUCUACUGGUUCUGCAACAACCUGAUUAAGGAGCUGCUGAAGGAGACGCGGAAGGAGCACACGCUGCGGGCAGUGGAGCUGCUCUACUCCAUCUUCUGCCUGGACAUGCAGCAAGUGACCCUGGUCCUGCUGGGCCACAUCCUACCUGGCCUGCUCACUGACUCCUCCAAGUGGCACAGCCUCAUGGACCCCCCGGGCACUGCUCUUGCCAAGCUGGCCGUGUGGUGUGCCCUCAGUUCCUACUCCUCCCACAAGGGACAGGCGUCCACCCGCCAGAAGAAGAGACACCGCGAAGACAUUGAGGAUUAUAUCAGCCUCUUCCCCCUGGACGAUGUGCAGCCUUCGAAGUUGAUGCGACUGCUGAGCUCUAAUGAGGACGAUGCCAACAUCCUUUCGAGCCCCACAGACCGAUCCAUGAGCAGCUCCCUCUCAGCCUCUCAGCUCCACACGGUCAACAUGCGGGACCCUCUGAACCGAGUCCUGGCCAACCUGUUCCUGCUCAUCUCCUCCAUCCUGGGGUCUCGCACCGCUGGCCCCCACACCCAGUUCGUGCAGUGGUUCAUGGAGGAGUGUGUGGACUGCCUGGAGCAGGGUGGCCGUGGCAGCGUCCUGCAGUUCAUGCCCUUCACCACCGUGUCGGAACUGGUGAAGGUGUCAGCCAUGUCCAGCCCCAAGGUGGUUCUGGCCAUCACGGACCUCAGCCUGCCCCUGGGCCGCCAGGUGGCUGCUAAAGCCAUUGCUGCACUCUGAGGGGCUUGGCAUGGCCGCAGUGGGGGCUGGGGACUGGCGCAGCCCCAGGCGCCUCCAAGGGAAGCAGUGAGGAAAGAUGAGGCAUCGUGCCUCACAUCCGCUCCACAUGGUGCAAGAGCCUCUAGCGGCUUCCAGUUCCCCGCUCCUGACUCCUGACCUCCAGGAUGUCUCCCGGUUUCUUCUUUCAAAAUUUCCUCUCCAUCUGCUGGCACCUGAGGAGAGUGAGCAGCCUGGACCACAAGCCCAGUGGUCACCCCUGUGUGCGCCCGCCCCAGCCCAGGAGUAGUCUUACCUCUGAGGAACUUUCUAGAUGCAAAGUGUGUAUGUGUGUGUGUGUGUGUGUGUGUGUGUGUUUGUGUGUAUUUUGUAAUAUGUGAGGGAAAUCUACCUUCGUUCAUGUAUAAAUAAAGCUCCUCGUGGCUCCC